AGGCUCGGACCGGCCCGCGGAGCUGCUGCAGUCCUUCGCGCCCUCCUCGCCCUCCCCACCGACAUCAUGCUCCAGUUCCUGCUUGGAUUUACACUGGGCAACGUGGUUGGAAUGUAUCUGGCUCAGAACUAUGAUAUACCAAACCUGGCUAAAAAACUUGAAGAAAUUAAAAAGGACUUGGAUGCCAAGAAGAAACCCCCUAGUGCAUGAGACUGCCUCCAGCACUGCCUUCAGGAUAUACUGAUUCUACUGCUCUUGAGGGCCUCGUUUACUAUCUGAACCAAAAGCUUUUGUUUUCGUCUCCAGCCUCAGCACUUCUCUUCUUUGCUAGACCCUGUGUUUUUUGCUUUAAAGCAAGCAAAAUGGGGCCCCAAUUUGAGAACUACCCGACAUUUCCAACAUACUCACCUCUUCCCAUAAUCCCUUUCCAACUGCAUGGGAGGUUCUAAGACUGGAAUUAUGGUGCUAGAUUAGUAAACAUGACUUUUAAUGAGUAGUGUCUUCUUUAUCGUUUGCGAUUUUUACUACCUUUUUUCAAAAGAAAAAUUGAUGAGUUUUGUAUAGCUGGUCAGAUACAAAUAAUAGUGACUUCACAGUUUAGUAAUUAUAAUGGGUACUUGUUAAACAUUUGGUACUAAAUUAUGUUGCUGCAAAGUAAUUAAAAUUAGUAUCUAGAGCUAGUUUCUGGUGAAUUAUUCAUUUAUUUUGUACUGUUGUUAGGCAGCUCUGUAGUUGCUAAUUUAACCAAUAAGUCAAUUUGCUAUUCAUGAAGAAACGAUUCUGAGAAUCCUGUCAGGAAUUGGGGAAUGAAAAAAUACACAAAAUAAUGGUCUUUGUCCCAGUAGAGUUCAUAGUCUAUUUAGUGUGCAUGUUUUUCCUUAAUGAUGUAUUUGAUCUGACUUUUUUCCUUCUCAAAAGAAUCAUACUUGGGAUUACAGGUACAUUUGAUGUUAUAUGAUGGAUAAGUGAAAAGUUUUUAAAGGAGAUUUUAUACCUUUUCACAUUAAAAAAGGUAUUUAUAUUAUUACUUUGUAGUGAUUGUCUUAAGAAAAAAUAUAGCCCAAAUGUAUAGUAAAAUCAGCAGCUCAAGAAGAAUUUCUGCUUCUCUUUGUAGUUGAUGCUUUGUUUUUUCCUGCAGUCAGAAAUUCCUUGUAUUUGUCAAAUGUAUAAUCAGCUUGUAUUGUUUUUAAAUUAAAAAAAAAUUUGAAUAAUUAACUUUUGCCAUGGGACAAGAUACAAAAGUAAUUUCAUAUAAAGGGCCUCUCCCACCCCUGUUCUCUGGCUCCUGGCUCCUGUUUGACAAGUUACUGUUACCACUUCGCCUUAUACUUUUGAGAAAGAGUCUGUGCCUAAACAAACACGUGUAACACAAAUAGUAACUAUACAUGGAGGUCUAGCCCUCGCCUUUUUUUUUUCUUUUUUUCUUUUUUAAUGGAGAUCAUUCUAUACCAGCAUGUAAGUAGCAAGGAACCUCAUUCUUUUUUUGGCUGCCUAAAAUUUUUUUGAAUAGAUAUAACAUAAUUGAUUUAAUCUGCUACUGGUGAAUGCUUAGGUUGUUCUUUUGCUAUUACAGUGAUAACUUCAAUCCUAAUGUUAUUAAGCAUAUCGAUUCAGGGUAUAGCUAUAAGAUGAAGUCCUAAAAGUAUAAUUUAGACUAAAUACAAAUACCCAUUUCGCUAGCUGUUUUGUUUCAGAGGACUUGUUGAGCAGCUUCACUAAUAAUGCCAUUUUUGAAGACAUGGCAGGUUCAGAAUCAAUAAACUGGAAGAAUUGUUCAGAGCAUCUUUUUUCAGACAGUGAUGACAUUGAUUCUGUAUAUGAUAAAGUGAUUCUGCUUCUCUUUGACAACUUGCAUCUCUCCUACAUGGAAGUAAGUUUUAUUCCUGUCAAUGUUGUCUUUGUGUGUGACAGAUUAGGAUUAAAUUAUGGUUUGACUUUUCCUAGCAGCGUGAUCAUGGGCAAGUGGCUUUUUUUUUUUUUUUUUUUUGAGACAGAGUCUCACUCUGCUGCCCAGGCUGGAGUGCAGUGGCACAGUCUUGGCUCACUGCAACUCCUGCCUCCCGGUCCAAGUGAUUCUCGUGCUGCAGCUUCUCAAGUAGCUGGCAUCACCACCACACCUGGCUAAUUUUUGUAUUUUUAGUAACGACGAGGUUUCACCAUGUUGGCAAAGCUGGUCUCAAAUUCCUGGCCUCAAGUGAUCUGCCCACUUCAGCCUCCCAAAGUGUUGGGAUUACAGGCGUGAGCCACUGCGCCCAGCUUUUUUAAACUUUUAGAUUCAUUUAAUAGGUAAAUUGCAUGUCACGGGUUUGUAGCUUAUUCUUUCAGAAACUCUUGCAUUAUCUGUAGACGUGGACGUAAAUAUCCACCUCAUAGGGUUUUCAUAAAAAAUAAUUGAGAUAAUGUAUGUAAUGUUUCACAGUGCUUUGCAGACUAUCUAAUAAAUAGUAGCUAUUAGUACAAA